GGGCAGGCUUUCUGGCUGGAUGCGCCUCCCCUGGAGCUACCUUUUGCUCAUCACAGCAGGUACUGUGUGUGUGUGUGUAUGUGCAUGUGUGUUUUCAGGUUUUUUACUGUGAUAAAACACACAAAACGCACCACCUUAACCAUUUCCAGGCGUGGUCGGUGGUGUUACAUUCACGCUGUUGCAGGCGUGCAGGUCGGUGGUGUUACACACAUUCACACUGUUGCAGGCGUGCAGGUCGGUGGUGUUACACACAUUUGGGCUGUUGCAGGCGUACAGGUCAGUGGUGUUACACACAUGCUGUUGCAGGAGUACAGGUCGGUGGUGUUACACACAUUCAUGCUGUUGCAGGCGUGCAGGUUGGUGCUGUUACACACAUGCUGUUGCAGGAGUACAGGUCGGUGGUGUUACAUGCUGUUGCAGGCGUGCAGGUCGGUGGUGUUACAUUCACGCUGUUGCAGGCGUGCAGGUCGGUGCUGUUACACACAUUCCUGCUGUUGCAGGAGUACAGGUCGGUGGUGUUACACGUGCUGUUGCAGGUGUGCAGGUCGGUGGUGGUACACACAUUCAUGCUGUUGCAGGAGUAUAGGUCGGUGGUGUUACACACAUUCACUGUUGCAGGCGUGCAGGUCGGUGGUGUUACACAUUCACGCUGUUGCAGGCGUGCAGGUCGGUGGUGUUACAUUCACGCUGUUGCAGACGUGCAGGUCAGUGCUGUUACACACGCUGUUGCAGGCGUGCAGGUUGGUGGUGUUACAUUCACACUGUUGCAGGCGUGCAGGUCGGUGGUGUUACACACAUUCAUUCUGUUGCAGGCGUGCAGGUCAGUGUUACACACAUUCACGCUGUUGCAGGCGUGCAGGUCGGUGGUGUUACACACAUUCACGCUGUUGCAGAUGUGCAGGUCGGUGCUGUUACAUUCACGCUGUUGCAAGCGUGCAGGUCGGUGGUGUUACAUUCACGCUGUUGCUGGCGUGCAGGUCGGUGGUGUUACACACAUUCACACUGUUGCAGACAUGCAGGUCGGUGCUGUUACACACAUUCAUGCUGUUGCAGGCGUGCAGGUCGGUGGUGUUACAUUCACACUUGCAGGCGUGCAGGUCGGUGGUGUUACACACAUUCAUGCUGUUGCAGGCGUGCAGGUCGGUGGUGUUACACACAUUCACACUGUUGCAGGCGUGCAGGUCGGUGGUGUUACAUUCAUGCUGUUGCAGGCGUGCAGGUCAGUGGUGUUACACACAUUCACGCUGUUGCAGGCAUGCAGGUCGGUGGUGUUACACACAUUCACGCUUUUGCAGGCGUGCAGGUCGGUGGUCUUACAUUCAUACUGUUGCAGGCGUGCAGGUCGGUGGUGUUACAUUCACACUGUUGCAGGCGUGCAGGUUGGUGUUACACACAUUCACACUUGCAGGCGUGCAGGUCGGUGGUGUUACACACAUGCUGUUGCAGGCGUGCAGGUCGGUGGUGUUACAUUCACACUGUUGCAGGCGUGCAGGUCGGUGGUACACACAUUCACACUGUUGCAGGCGUGCAGGUCGGUGGUGUUACACACAUUCAUGGUGUUGCAGGCGUGCAGGUCGGUGUUACACACAUGCUGUUGCAGGCGUGCAGGUCGGUGGUACAUUCAUGCUGUUGCAGGCGUGCAGGUCGGUGGUGUUACACAUUUUCACGCUGUUGCAGACGUGCAGGUCAGUGGUGUUACAUUCAUGCUGUUGCAGGCGUGCAGGUCGGUGGUGUUACAUUCACGCUGGUGCAGGCAUGCAGGUCGGUGGUGUUACACACAACGCUGUUGCAGGCGUGCAGGUCAGUGGUACACACAUUCACGCUAUUGCAGGCGUGCAGGCCGGUGGUGUUACAUUCACGCUGUUGCAGGCGUGCAGGUUGGUGUUACACACAUUCACACUUGCAGGCGUGCGGGUCGGUGGUGUUACACACAUUCAUGCUGUUGCAGGCGUGCAGGUCGGUGGUGUUACACACAUUCACACUGUUGCAGGCGUGCAGGUCCGUGGUGUUACACACAUGCUGUUGCAGGCGUGCAGGUCGGUGGUGUUACAUUCACACUGUUGCAGGUGUGCAGGUUGGUGUUACACACAUUCACACUGUUGCAGGCUUGCAGGUCGGUGGUGUUACACACAUUCACACUUGCAGGCGUGCAGGUCAGUGGUGUUACACACAUUCAUGCUGUUGCAGGCAUGCAGGUCGGUAGUGUUACACAUUCAUGCUGUUGCAGGCGUGCAGGUCGGUGGUGUUGCACAUUCAUGCUGUUGCAGGCAUGCAGGUCGGUGGUGUUACAUUCACGCUGUUGCAGGAGUACAGGUCAGUGGUGUUACACACAUUCAUGCUGUUGUGCAGCUAUCACUUCCAUCUCCAGAGCCCUUUUCAUCUUAAAACUGAAGCUCUCCCAUCACACAGUGACCCUUCAUGUCCCUCCCCAGUCCCUGAAAAACACUGUUCAGGUUUUUCUUCCUGGACCUCAUUGUGUGGAGUUCCUCGUGUGAGUGCAGUCACACACGAUUUGUCCUUUUUUUGUUUUCGUUUGUUGAGACAGAGUCUCAUUCUGUCACUCAGGCUGGAGUGCAGUGGCGUGAUCUCAGCUCACUGCAACCUCCACUCCCAGGUUCAAGUGAUUCUCCUGCCUCAGCCUCCCAAGUAGCUGGGAUUACAGGCGCCUGCCACCACGCCCAGCUAAUUUUUGUGUUUUUAUUAGAGACAGGGUUUCACCAAGUUGGCCAGACUGGUCUCAAACUCCUGACCUCGUGAUCCACCCGCCUGGGCCUCCCACAGUGCUGGGAUGACAGGCGUGAGCUACCACACCCGGCUGAUUUAUCCUUUUAUUUGGGCUCCUUUCACUCAGCGUCUUUAAGCUUCAUACGCGAAAGAUGCUUCAGAGAUUCCUUUUUCAGGCUGAAUAUCUGCUGCGUGGCUAGGCCACUUUUUGUUUAAUCCUCUCUCCUCUGGUGGACACCAGGACUGUGCUGUUUUGGUUGCUGUAAGCGCGGGUGCACACGCCUGCCUGAGGCUGUGUUUUGGCCGUUGUGAGUGUGGGUGCACACACCUGCCUGAGGCUCUGCUUUGUUGUGAGUGCGGGUGCACACACCUGCCUGAGGCUGUGUUUUGGGUGUUGUGAGUGUGGGUGCACACACCUGCCUGAGGCUGUGUUUUGGGUGUUGUGAGUGUGGGUGCACACACCUGCCUGAGGCUGUGGCGCGAUCUCGGCUCACUGCAACCUCCACCUCCCGGGUUCAAGCGAUUCUCCUGCCUCAG